GAGAGCCGGGUGGAUGGGUCAGAGGCUCCGCGAUGGAGUUGGGAUGGGGAUGGGGAGGAGUGGCCGCCUUAGGCAUCGGGUGAGGGGUGGUGGUAAGUGGACACAGGAGGAGGACUAGGAAGUCAGGGCCUGGCUGGGGAGACAGGUGAAGGGUCUGAGGACAUGCAGAGGGGGCUGAGAUGCGGGCCGGAGUAACCGUGGUGCCCAAGCAGCUGGUGCGGAAGAGGAGGCUUUUGGAACAAGCUUGGGAUGACUGCUUGGGACGUGGGGAGACUUGGGCGAGGAGGCCAGAAAAUGUUGGGUAGGGUCCGAAGUGGAGAAGGCCGGGAAGUUACCGGGGUCGAGGCUGGUCCGGAAAGAGAGUAUGUUGGGAUGAGUAUACCUGCCGUUGGAGAUGGGGGAGACCAGGGCAGGGCCAGCUUGUUUCUAGGGGAUUCUCAGUCUUGGUGCAAAGAGAUGGGGAAAUUCUUUGAGGAAUUGAGGGGUCCAUGGAGCCGUGAACUGAGGAGAGAUGGUGGAAGGGGUGGGGAGCUCUUGAGUAGUGAAGAGGGGUGCGUGGGAAACUGGUGACUUCUGGAAGGAGUUGCAGGAUGACGGGUUUGCUCCUGAAAUCCAGGGGACUGGGGGACAGGUGGAGAUGUUUGGUGUGCUAAAUCUUUCAAGUACAAGAUGAGCCAUCGUUGAAGCUCAGGGUUCCAAUCGAGUAAUCCUGCCUGUGUCUGUAGAUGAGUAUCAAGUGGGGCAGCUGUAUUCUGUGGCUGAGGCCAGUAAAAAUGAAACGGGUGGUGGCGAAGGCGUGGAGGUCCUGGUGAAUGAGCCCUACGAGAAGGACGGUGAGAAAGGCCAGUACACACACAAGAUCUACCACCUGCAGAGCAAAGUACCCACGUUUGUUCGAAUGCUGGCCCCAGAGGGAGCCCUGAAUAUACACGAGAAAGCCUGGAAUGCUUACCCCUACUGCAGAACCGUUAUUACAAAUGAGUACAUGAAAGAAGACUUUCUGAUUAAAAUUGAAACCUGGCACAAACCAGAUCUUGGCACGCAGGAGAAUGUGCAUAAGCUGGAGCCUGAGGCGUGGAAACACGUGGAAGCCGUAUAUAUAGACAUUGCAGAUCGAAGCCAAGUGCUCAGCAAGGAUUACAAGGCAGAGGAAGACCCAGCAAAAUUUAAAUCUAUCAAAACAGGCCGAGGACCCUUGGGCCCCAAUUGGAAGCAAGAGCUUGUAAACCAGAAGGACUGCCCAUAUAUGUGUGCAUACAAACUGGUGACCGUCAAGUUCAAGUGGUGGGGCCUGCAGAACAAAGUGGAGAACUUCAUCCAUAAGCAAGAGAGGCGUCUGUUUACAAACUUCCACAGGCAGCUGUUCUGUUGGCUCGAUAAGUGGGUUGACCUGACCAUGGACGACAUUCGAAGGAUGGAAGAAGAGACGAAGAGACAGCUGGAUGAAAUGAGACAAAAGGACCCAGUGAAAGGAAUGACAGCAGAUGACUAAAGCCGCCUUUCCCCUCUGCACUUUUUGCAAGACAGUGGUCAACAGGAAGACCCAGCAGCUCCACCCUCCCAAGUGACAGGCCAUUUUCGGACGCAGCCGUUCUGUGCCCAUUCUUCAGGCAACUUUCGAUUCCUUACUGUAGCUAAUUCUAGAUGCCCUUCAGUAUUGUGAACAAAUAGACCGUCUGGUGUCACAGAGCCCGCGUGUGCAGGAGCCUGCUCCUCCGAGAUACGUGGCGUGUAGGUUGCUGUAGUUACAGCGCCUCCGUCUCUCUCCAUUGUGUUCCGAUCCAUUUCUGUGUGUUCCCCCAACCUUUAUUUCCAAGUGACAUUUUCAGUCUUUCAAAUAGCUGCCUUUUGUGAUGUGGUGAUUUAAAUGAUUUAAGUUCAUUUGUUCUCAACCUUGGGGUAAACUGAGGUAUUUUGCUUCCUGGGAAGAUCUUCGCAAUUUUGAGUGCUCCUGUGGGGAGCGGGGAUGAGCUAAAGAUACAAUGUUUCCCUGCCCCGCACCGCUUCCACAAAAUAGCAAUGUGGUUUUGCAGCUCUGACUUCUGCUCCCAGUAACCCAUCGUUAGGGCACUCUAGCACUAUGGAGGUACCCAAGGCUCAGCCAGUCUCUAUUUAAGAAAAUUUAACAAAUACGAGUAACCCUGUCCCAAUCACUGAAUCUCUAGUUACUACUCUUAGAAACACCUGUGGCUUCUUGGCCCUCCUGUUGCCCGCUCUGAAUCUCUCUGCAGUCUACAAAAUCGCCCCAGUCAACUCUCCACUUGGAGGGAAUUGUCCAGUGUGGCCCCUAGAAUUGAGUCACCCCCUAGAUACCAACUGUCUGACCCCGAGGAGCUCUGUAAGUCCCUGCUCCUCCUCUUCCCUUUGGGGCUGGUGCUGCCACUCAGCAAUAAUCCUCUUUUCUCUGUGCUUUCUUAGGUCCCUGUCCUCUGUCUUUGAGGCUGGUUAGGAAGCAAGAGUCCUGAUCUUUCAUGCUGCACAAUAUGAGCAUGCAAAAAGCUUUUUCCAGCAGAACAUGUUCCCUCGUCUCCAGUUGCCGGAAAGGAAUUUGGGGAUCAAGAACUUAGCUCGUCCUACCCCCAUGUUGAGUUCUGCCCUGGAAAACCCAAAGCAAGUAGUGAUCAUAGUACAGAACCCGACCAAAGUAGGCUGGUGAGGAAGUCCAGGCUCCAGGGGAACAGACGCUGCCCAGUGUUCAUAGCUUCCUGCAACUUGACAGAGCCUGAGUUUGCCUCUUAGUGGGAGAAUGAGAGAGAGCUGUAGUGUCACCUGACAUUCCCCAAACCUUGUGAAGCACGUUGGCCUAAGUGUGCCGUGAUCCCAGCCCACACUAGCCUGGGUGCAUCUGCUAAUGGGAGACCAAAUCUUUGUCCGGGAAGCAAGAAGUGGGUGGGAGAAUGUAUCCUGUUUUUGUCAGUUUGUUUGCCUUACUCAUUUCUAAGUGCAAUAAGGGAGUGUCUCACAGGAUUGCACCUGUGACAUCCUGAUGGAUGCUUCCCUGUGGCCCUCCUGGGGCAAGGGUGGACAGACUCAGACCCCCAGCAUGGUUAGCGCUGACCUUCAUUGAGGUCCCUUUGGAACCAGAUGUCUUGUUACAGACACCUUCCUCUGUGUAAGUCUCCUCACCUUGAGGGGUCUUUAGUAAUGCAUCUGGGUAGCAUCUCAACUGCUGGUAGCAUUUAUCUGACUUGGAAAGUUGGAGAAGAGGCAUUCCUACUGGAGAAAAAUGUCAGUGUUUUCCUAUAAGCUCUGUGUUAGCUAUUCAUUAUAUUUGUGCUUAAAGAUGUUCCUUCAUUCAUCAACUAGGGGAAGUCCAGAUGCGGGUUAUCUUGAAAGAAACAAACUGACAUUCUAGGCAGACAGUUGUCUAUGUGGUCUGAGGGUCAGCAGCUGUUAGUCUCCUUCCUUUGGCUCUUGAGACCCACACAUAUCACUUUAGCCCUAACAAGGGCUCCUCCCACCUCCACCUGUUGCCCCAGUUGAAAAGCAUCCAUUAUGAGCUGAGGUCAGCCUGGAUCUGGAAUUGCAGCCCACAUAAACAUAAAGGAGGAUGUCCCUGGUCUGUUCCAUCCCCACGGAUGGUGUUGCUGCUGGGCAACAGUGUUGGCUUCUUUUAAGUACCCCCUUUCCUCCUCACCCACCUCCAAACUGACUAGCACUCAGAGGGACUUAUGAUAAAGGUUCAGCUCCAGGGGUAGUACCUGAGUGUGUGCCAUGCCCCUUCAGACCAGCUGCUUCCAUCAGAAUUCCAGGGUCACAGCCCCAACAGAAGCAGCAGUGCCUCUGUAGGAGGGGUGCUGGGCUCUGGCCUUCUCAUGCAGAGAGGUCCGGGACAGGGUCAGUAUCGUGGGCAUGUGUAUAGCUUCCCAAGUUCUUUUACAGUCCCUGCUGGGACUCCCUGACUUACUUUGGUUGGUUCCUAGUGCUACUUGUUUUACAAACUACACUUUGUAGAAUUGAUUAGAUUACCUUGUUUAUUUAAUGUGAGUUUGUGCCUUUUUGUCUCAAUCUUCCAAUACAGGUAUAUUGAGAAAAAAAGCAGUCUAAUAAAAUCCUAGACAGAACUUUCUGGAGUCCAGUUUGGUGAUGUCCAUUUUCCAGCUGUAUGUAUCCUCAAACUUGCACUGAUAACCGCCAUUUUACCAGGGCAGGAUUAGGAAGAGGUACAAAGGUGUGUCUGAAAAUUUUUGCACGUGGAUUUCUGCAUAUAAUAGUCCCGUGUCAGUUUACUUAUGCAAACAUUGCACAUCUGAAUUGUAAUUCGGCCGUUUCCUACUGACAGGAUGUCCUUUUGCUUUUGUCUGCCUCCUCUUCACAUCUUCCUCUUUAUCCACC